GCUUGAACUCGGCGGCUUCCGUAGCGGGAGGGCGAAAGAUGGCGGCGGCAGUACUGGGACAGUUGGGUGCGUUAUGGAUACAUAACCUGAGGAGCCGGGGGAAGCUGGCCUUGGGUGUUUUACCUCAAUCAUAUAUCCACACAAGUGCUUCUCUUGACAUUUCUCGAAAAUGGGAGAAGAAGAAUAAAAUUGUUUAUCCUCCACAACUGCCUGGAGAACCUCGGAGACCAGCAGAAAUCUACCACUGUCGAAGACAAAUAAAAUAUAGCAAAGACAAGAUGUGGUAUUUGGCAAAAUUGAUACGAGGAAUGUCUAUUGACCAGGCUUUGGCUCAGUUGGAAUUCAAUGACAAAAAAGGGGCCAAAAUAAUUAAAGAGGUUCUCUUAGAAGCACAAGAUAUGGCAGUGAGAGACCAUAACGUGGAAUUCAGGUCCAAUUUAUAUAUAGCUGAGUCCACCUCAGGACGAGGCCAGUGCCUGAAACGCAUCCGCUACCAUGGCAGAGGUCGCUUUGGGAUCAUGGAGAAGGUUUAUUGCCAUUAUUUUGUGAAGUUGGUGGAAGGGCCCCCACCUCCACCUGAGCCACCAAAGACGGCAGUUGCCCAUGCCAAAGAGUAUAUUCAGCAGCUUCGCAGCCGGACCAUCGUUCACACUCUAUGAUGAGGAGAUUCAGACUCCACAGUGUAUAUAUUUUGCCAUUUAUUUUCUAAAAAUAAACAAAAAUUGAAGGCAAAUGCUUUUUAUGAUUUCUCAUUGAAUUAUUGAAACAGUGUAUAACUGCUAGUUGUAAAUGAAUAUUUAUAAGGCUUUGCCCAUUUCUUUUGAGCCUCUGGGCAUAUUUGUAUGCAUUUGCGACUUGGAAGGGGAAAUCAGCUUUAAACAUAGUAACAGACUAUAUUUCAAAAGGCUUUUGGAGUAACUUUGAAAGGGAAUGUUAACUUUCCAACUAGUGUCCUGCAGGUGGCUGUUUUGAUACUGGACUUGAAUACAGUGUUAUGAGGUAAGAAAAUUGCUUUUAUUUCACUUAAUUUUCUCUUGGGACCAUGGGAAGUUAGAGUGGCUGCAUGUUGUUUCAUUACAGUAUUUUAGGGUGUUCAGUGGUACCGUUUUUCCUUUCACUGUUGGCACAGGCCAGUGAGUCAAAAAUUAUAUUUUCCUUUACUGUUUUAGCAGUAACUCGAAACUACAGGAGUUUAUUAGAUAUACGAAUCUAAAACUCCAAAAACCUUUAACUUUGAAAAUUUUCUUUUGGUUAAGCAAAGCCUGUUUUUAUUUCUUCUUCCAACAGUGCUUUAUAUUGUUUGGAUAUCUUGUUUAGGAUUGAUUUAUUUUUCAGGGUAAAUUCAAUUACUGAGAGAGGAAUUGAACCAAUCUCAGCAUUGCAUUCUAAAAUGGGGCAGUAGGUGGCACUCAACCUUUUAUUAGCAGAAAAUUGUUAGUUUCAAAUUAGAGUGUUCAACACUGCUUCCCUCUCAUUCAUACACGUCUUCAUUAAGAAGAAGUACUCUUUGUCUACAGCCCUAGUCCAACUUUUGCAUGCAAAAGAAGAAUCGAGGAUGCUUGCUUGUUAAUGCAGACUUCUGGGCCCCACCCCAAUGAUUCAAUUCACUAGGUCUUAUGGGGGGCUGGUUUCAGAAAUCUAUGUUUUAAACAAACACUUCCAGGUAAUUCUGUUGUAGGGGACUACGCUUUGAGAAUACGGCUUUAGGAGAAUGAAAAAAUGUAGUUUUAUUGCCAUGUUUUAAGAUGGCAUUAAUAAUAGUUACUGUUUACUGGGAACUUGUUAUUUGCAAGCUCUGUGCUAGUAUUUUACAUAAUUCUUCACAACAUCCUGAAAAUGUAGCUUUUGUUUUACCACUUUACAAAGGAAUAAACCGAAGCACACAGAAUUCAAAUAACUAUCACAAGUCACACAGCAUGUAAAUAUUGGGGCUAUGAUUGAAAGGUUUCUAAAGUAGCUGGUUCUGCAUACCUUUUGAGUAUACAGCUGGGUUUUUGUGUCUCUCCAGUUAACCUAAUGCAUGGGUAAAAAGACAUCAGGGGUCAGUGGAAUAAACCAAGGUGUAGGACAGAUUCAUUCUGGGUCCUAAGCUGUUGUAGCAUGGAGUCAGGGAAAUAACACUGGAAUAUUAAAAGGUAACCUUCAUUCUAGUCUGUGCAUUCUCAUUAGCCAGAAAGAAGACUGGAUAGGUCUCUUCCCUUGCUGGCCUCCAUUUCAUUCAUUUAUGAAACAAGAGACUCAAUGUUCUCUGUAGAAAACCUUUUUUAGAAUCACUUGAAGAAUUUGUUUAAAAAUGCAAAUUCCUGGGCUCUACUCUCAGACUAAGUGAAUCAGAAGCUUUGGUGUGGGAGACCAUGGAACCUGCAGUUUUAAUAAAUGCCCCAGUGAUUUGCAUGUUGGAGAAUUAUCACACCAGGUCACUGUGCUCUCAUGUGGUGGGGAUGCUCCACGAUUGCUCUUGGAGUUGUGACUUCCUUGGGUGUGACUAAAGCCAGGUGGUGCCAUGGACAUCAUAAAUAUAAAUUAUGUAAGUGAAGGCACUGCUUCAGUCAGGCUGUAAAAGCUAUUUUGAAAGUGGUAAGGAAAAAGUAGGAUUGUAAUGAAGAAAAUUUCCUUCCCAGGUUAAGCCUUCAUUUGGAACUGCUUCCAGUACGUUACAAAAAGUAAUAAUAGCUAACCUGUGUCACUGACUGUAUCUGGUACUAUUUUAAGCACUAUAUAUACAUUAUCUCAAUGAAUCUUUCCCAUUGUGACAUCCGGCUAGUUUUCGUGGCUAAGAGUGUACUUUCUAACAUCCAUGAACAUUGUGGUCCCCACCUGAAGUUUCACUUUGCAUGUUCAGUGAUAUGGUUUGGCUCUGUGUUCCCACCCAAUCUUAUCUCAAAUUGUAAUCCCCAUGUGUCCAGGGAGGGACCUGUAAUCCCCACCUAGUGACGGAGGGAGGUGAUUGAUGAUGGGUGUGGUGUACCCCAUGCUGUUCUCGUGAUAGUGAGUGGGUUCUCAUGAGAUCUGAUGGUUUUAUAAGUGUUUGAAAGUUCCCUCUUCACUCGCUGUCUUGCCUGCUGCCAUGUAAAAUGUGCCUACUUCACCCUCUGCCAUGAUUGUAAGUUUCCUGAGGCCUCCCCAGCCAUGCAGAACUUUGACACAAUUAAAUGUCUUUUCUUUAUAAAUUA